GGGACUUCCGCCGUCCUCCUGGUGGUGGUCGUUUUGGUUCUGUGUGGUGUUUCACCAACUUCGGCCUAUGGCUCUGUCUGACGUCACCGAAGUGACGGAACGGAAAAGCGCGAGAAGCGGCUCGGUUCCCACCACGGAGAGGCGGGAGUGAGUCAACUGACAAGCGCUGGGGACAGUGGCGUCCUUGUCUUGCCUUUGUCGCUCCCGCCCCGCUCUUCCCUGGCUGGGCUGGCGGAGGCCUUGCUGAUGAACCUGACUGAGGGUCCCCUGGCGAUGGCAGAAAUGGACCCUACACAGGGCCGUGUGGUCUUUGAGGACGUGGCCAUAUAUUUCUCCCAGGAGGAGUGGGGGCACCUUGAUGAGGCUCAGAGAUUGCUGUACCGUGAUGUGAUGCUGGAGAAUUUGGCCCUUUUGUCCUCACUAGGUUCUUGGCAUGGAGCUGAGGAUGAGGAGGCACCUUCACAGCAAGGUUUUUCUGUAGGAGUGUCAGAGGUUACAGCUUCAAAGCCCUGUCUGUCCAGCCAGAAGGUCCACCCUAGUGAGACAUGUGGCCCACCCUUGAAAGACAUUCUGUGCCUGGUUGAGCACAAUGGAAUUCAUCCUGAGCAACACAUAUAUAUUUGUGAGGCAGAGCUUUUUCAGCACCCAAAGCAGCAAAUUGGAGAAAAUCUUUCCAGAGGGGAUGAUUGGAUACCUUCAUUUGGGAAGAACCACAGAGUUCACAUGGCAGAGGAGAUCUUCACAUGCAUGGAGGGCUGGAAGGACUUACCAGCCACCUCAUGCCUUCUCCAGCACCAGGGCCCUCAAAGCGAGUGGAAGCCAUACAGGGACACAGAGGACAGAGAAGCCUUUCAGACUGGACAAAAUGAUUACAAAUGUAGUGAAUGUGGGAAAACCUUCACCUGCAGCUAUUCAUUUGUUGAGCACCAGAAAAUCCACACAGGAGAAAGGUCUUAUGAAUGUAACAAAUGUGGGAAAUUCUUUAAGUACAGUGCCAAUUUCAUGAAACAUCAGACAGUUCACACUAGUGAAAGGACUUAUGAGUGCAGAGAAUGUGGAAAAUCCUUUAUGUACAACUACCGACUCAUGAGACAUAAGCGAGUUCACACUGGAGAAAGGCCUUAUGAGUGCAACACAUGUGGGAAAUUCUUUCGGUACAGCUCCACAUUUGUUAGACAUCAGAGAGUUCACACCGGAGAAAGGCCGUAUGAGUGCAGGGAAUGUGGGAAAUUCUUUAUGGACAGCUCCACACUCAUUAAACAUCAGAGAGUUCACACCGGAGAAAGACCUUAUAAGUGCAAUGAUUGUGGGAAAUUUUUUAGGUAUAUCUCCACACUCAUUAGACAUCAGAGAAUUCACACUGGAGAAAGGCCUUAUGAGUGCAGUGUAUGUGGGGAAUUGUUUAGGUACAACUCCAGCCUUGUUAAACAUUGGAGAAAUCACACUGGAGAAAGGCCUUAUAAAUGCAGUGAAUGUGGGAAAUCAUUUAGGUACCACUGCAGGCUCAUUAGACACCAGAGAGUCCACACGGGAGAAAGGCCUUAUGAGUGCAGCGAAUGCGGGAAAUUCUUUCGUUACAACUCCAACCUCAUUAAACAUUGGAGAAAUCACACUGGAGAAAGGCCUUACGAGUGCAGAGAGUGUGGGAAAGCCUUUAGCCACAAGCAUAUACUUGUUGAGCACCAGAAAAUCCACAGUGGAGAAAGACCUUAUGAGUGCAGCGAAUGCCAGAAGGCCUUUAUUAGAAAGUCUCACCUGGUUCAUCACCAGAAAAUCCACAGUGAAGAGAGGCUUGUGUGCUCCAUGAAUGUGGGGAAUUCUUUAGCUAAAACUCCAACCUCAUUAAACAUCAGAGAUUUCACAAUGGAGAAAGUUUACCAUUGACUAUUGUAAUUGGGUAGUAAUGUUAUAUAAAUUCCACAUUUUUAUGCAACUAAUCUCCAGAACAUUUUUCCUCUUACCAAGAAGUAAAAUGCUGUACCCAUUAACAACAACUCAUUCCCCUUCCCUACUUCCCCAGAAAUGUCUCAACUAUAUUUCUAUACUCUAUGGUACUUAUAUGAGGUACCAAUAGAUAUCUAUGAAUUUGAUAUAUAUUUGUACCUCAUAUAAGUGGAUUCUACAGUAUUUAUCUUUUGAGACUGGCUUAUUUCACUUAGGAUAAGGUCUUCACGGUUCACCCAUGUUGUAUAAUGUGUCAGAAUAUCCUUCCUUUUUAGGUGAAAUAAUAUUCUAUGGUAUUUAUAUACCACAUUUAUUUAUCCAUUCAUCUGUUAGUGGAUACUUGGGCUACUUCCACCUUUUGCCUAUUGAAAUAAUGCUGCUAUGAAGAUGAGUGUACAAGUGUCUAUUCAAGAUUCUACUUUCAAUUCUUAUAGGGUAUAUACUCAGAAAUGGUGGUGCUGGAUCAUAUAGGAUUUCUAUUUUUUUUUUUUGUUUGUUUUUGAGACAGAGUCUUGCUCUGUCACCCAGGCUGGAGUGCAGUGCUGUGAUCUUGGCUCACUGCAAGCUCCGCCUCCCAGGUUCAUGCCAUUCUCCUGCCUCACCCUCCCGAGUAGCUGGGACUACAGGUGCCUGCCACCACGCCUGGCUAAUUUUUUUGUAUUUUUAGUAGAGACGGGGUUUCACCGUGUUAGCCAGGAUGGUCCUGAUCUCCUGACCUUGUGAUCUGCCUGCCUUGGCCUCUCAAAGUGCUGGGAUUACGGGCGUGAGCCACCGCGCCUGGCCAGGAUUUCUAUUUUUAAUAUUUUUGGGAAAAUUUUUCCAUAGUACCUGUGCCAUUUUACAUUCCCACCAGCAGUGCACAAGGAUUGCAAUCUAUAUACAUCCUCACCAACAUUGUUCAUUUUCUAUUUCUGUUUUUGGGGUUUUUUGUAGUGCCUUUUGUUUUGGAUAGCAGCUAUCUUGUUGGAUGUGAGGUGGAAUCUAUAGUGUCUUUCAUUUUUAUUUUGUGAAUGAUUGAUGAUGUUGAGGAUCUUUUCAUGUGCUUGUUAGGCAUUUGUGUAUCUGGAAAAAUAUUCAAGUCUUUUUUUUCCAUUUUUAAUGGGACUAUUUGCUUUUUGUUGUUGAGUUGUAGUUCUUUAUACAUUCUGGAUAUUAACUCCUUACCAAAUAUAUGCUUUUUACAUAUUACCUCCCAGUCCAUAGGUUGCUUUUUCGCUCUGUUGAUUGUGUCCUUUGAUGAAAUUUUAAGUUUUGAUGUACUGUUGACUCUUUCUGUCUGUGGGUUCUGUAUUCAUGGAUCGAAGCAACCAUGGAUCAAAAGUAUUUGGAGCAUCCAUGGAUUGCAGUGAUCAUUAAUCAAAAAUAUUUGGAAAACAAAAAGGGUAGUUGCAUCUGUACUAAACAUGAACAGACAUUUUUUCUUGUCAUUAUUCCCUAAACUAUAUAGUAUAAUAAAUAUUUACAUAGCAUUUACAUUGUAUUAGAAGUUAUAAAUAACCUAAUGAUAAUCUAUAUAGGAAGAUGUGUGUAGGUUAUAUUCAAACACUAUGCCUUUUUAUGUGAGGGACCUCUUGAGCAUCAGAUGAUUUUGGUAUCCACAAGGGGUCCUGGAAUCAGUCCCCCACAGACACCAAGGGAUGACUGUAGUGCAUUUUAUCUAUUUUUACUUCUGUUACCUGGGCUUUUGAUGUUAUAUAUUAAAAAAAAUUAGUAUCAAAUCCAAUGCCAAGCAUUUUCCCUAUGCUUUAUUCUAAGAAUUUUAUAUUUGAAGGUCUUACAUUUAGGUCUUUUUUUUUUUUUUCUUUUGGAGGCAGAGUCUUGCUCUGUCACCCAGCCUGGAGUGCAGUAGUGGAAUCUCAGCUCACUACAACCUCCGCCUCCUGGGUUCGAGCCAUCACCCCACCUCAGCCUCCCAAGUAGCUUGGAUUACAAGUGUACACCACCACACCUGGCUAAUUUUUGUAUUUUUAGUAGAGAUGGGGUUUUGCCAUGUUGGCCAGGCUGGUCUUAAACUUCUGGCCUUAAGUGAUCCCCCUGCCUCGGCCUCCCAAAUUGCUGAGAUUACAGGCAGGAGUUGUAAUGCACUGUGCCUGGCUACAUUUAGAUCUUUAAUCUACUUGGGGUUCAUUUUUGCAUAUGGUUUAAGGCAAAAGUCCACUUUAUGUGGCUAUCCAGUUUUCCAAGCACCAUUUUUUGAAAAGAGCAUCUUUCCUCUGUUGAGUAGUCUUGGCACACUUGUCAAAAUCAUUUGUCCAUAUAUGCCAUGGUUUAUAUGUGGAUUCUCUAUUUUAUUGGUCAUAUGUCUGUCUUUAUGUCAGUACCACACAUUUUAGGUGUGUGUGUGUGAGACUCAGUGUUGAGGACAAGGCUAGUGGGCUUUCACACUCCAGACUGCUGUAUUCCAGCCCAAAUUACUCAAAUUAGCCAAUCCAUGGGGAACAUGGAAAACGUAGCUAAUGCAAUCCGCUUGCCUUACCUAAGUUGUCCCCUGCAGCCUCAGGUUGCUGUUACUGUGUUUCAGAUGCAACCCUCUGUGGGACCCUACCCAAGUUCUCUCAUUCUUAGCUAUAGGUAAUAAAUUGUUCUGAUUUUGUGUAUCCAAGUGACAUUGGGUUGUUUCUUGCUAUCAGAAGAACCCAGAAAAGUAUUAUGAAUCUAGUGAAUGUUGGAAAAUCUUUAGCCAUUAGCAUAACCUCAUUUCGUGCCAGCAUGUUCACCCUAGAGAAAAGUAGAAGUGAAGGCAAUGUCAUCUUUCCUUGUUAACAUGAUAACUCAGUAGAGCAAUGCUUUGGAGAUUAGCUUUUUAGGGAGAGAGCCAGCAGUUGAGCCUCCUGCAUCUGAACAUCCACACUAGGGAUAUUGUCUGUACUGCCAGAUAUAUGGGAAGAUUUUGUGAACUGUGUUGCAGUUUUCAACUUGACUGGGGCCUUUCCCAGAGUUAUGCCCCUGCCAGUGCCUAUUUAAAAAUGUCAUCUCUUUUCUACCAACUGGCAAAGAGCCAUGGUGUGUAGCAUUUUAGUCACAUUAAAAUGCAGUUAUGGCA